CUUUCUCUCUCCUCCCGCCGCCCAAGAUGCCGAAAGGAAAGAAGGCCAAGGGAAAGAAGGUGGCUCCGGCCCCAGCUGUCGUGAAGAAGCAGGAGGCUAAGAAAGUGGUGAAUCCCCUGUUUGAGAAAAGGCCUAAGAAUUUUGGCAUUGGACAGGACAUCCAGCCCAAAAGAGACCUCACCCGCUUUGUGAAAUGGCCCCGCUAUAUCAGGUUGCAGCGGCAGAGAGCCAUCCUCUAUAAGCGGCUGAAAGUGCCUCCUGCGAUUAACCAGUUCACCCAGGCCCUGGACCGCCAAACAGCUACUCAGCUGCUUAAGCUGGCCCACAAGUACAGACCAGAGACAAAGCAAGAGAAGAAGCAGAGACUGUUGGCCCGGGCCGAGAAGAAGGCUGCUGGCAAAGGGGACGUCCCAACGAAGAGACCACCUGUCCUUCGAGCAGGAGUUAACACCGUCACCACCUUGGUGGAGAACAAGAAAGCUCAGCUGGUGGUGAUUGCACACGACGUGGAUCCCAUCGAGCUGGUUGUCUUCUUGCCUGCCCUGUGUCGUAAAAUGGGGGUCCCUUACUGCAUUAUCAAGGGAAAGGCAAGACUGGGACGUCUAGUCCACAGGAAGACCUGCACCACUGUCGCCUUCACACAGGUGAACUCGGAAGACAAAGGCGCUUUGGCUAAGCUGGUGGAAGCUAUCAGGACCAAUUACAAUGACAGAUACGAUGAGAUCCGCCGUCACUGGGGUGGCAAUGUCCUGGGUCCUAAGUCUGUGGCUCGUAUCGCCAAGCUCGAAAAGGCAAAGGCUAAAGAACUUGCCACUAAACUGGGUUAAAUGUACACUGUUGAGUUUUCUGUACAUAAAAAUAAUUGAAAUAAUACAAAUUUUCCUUCA